AGUGUUGCCUGGACCCCAAGGGCCCUUUACAUUGCGUUCUUAACGGUUCAGUCACCUUAACCGUUAUUAUUCACUUGCGGGCGAGAAGUCCGAGCUAGGGAUCCUGAAAAGGAGGGAACAAUUGUUGUAGCAGGUCUAAAAGUUCAGGUCCAGGAAAUGGAAACAUUGCUUUGCUUUUCCUGAAUUGUCCAGUGACCUAUCCCAGGCCUUCCUUUCCAGUGAACAAUGGACCAUGCAGGUGGACCCUCCUCUUCACGGGCCUCCAAAUGACUUUCUCAUUUUUCAAAUCAUUCCUCUGCACUCACUUUCUAUAAUGCCCCGGUUUCUCUGGAUUCUGUGCUUCUCCAUGGAGGAAACUCAAGGAGAACUGACAAGUUCUUGUGGUUCUAAAACCAUGGCCAAUGUAUCUUUGGCAUUUAGGGAUGUGUCCAUAGACCUCUCCCAAGAGGAGUGGGAGUGCCUGGACGCUGUGCAGAGGGACUUGUACAAGGAUGUGAUGUUGGAGAACUACAGCAACCUGGUCUCACUGGGAUAUACCAUUCCUAAGCCAGAUGUGAUUACUUUAUUGGAGCAAGAGAAAGAGCCCUGGAUAGUAAUGAGGGAAGGGACAAGGAAUUGGUUCACAGAUUUGGAAUACAAGUAUAUUACCAAGAAUUUGCUUUCAGAAAAGAAUGUUUGCAAAAUCUAUUUAUCUCAAUUGCAGACAGGGGAAAAAAGUAAAAACACCAUCCAUGAGGACACCAUUUUCAGAAAUGGUUUGCAGUGUAAACAUGAAUUUGAGAGACAAGAGAGACAUCAGAUGGGAUGCGUUAGUCAAAUGCUAAUCCAAAAACAAAUAUCUCAUCCUCUACAUCCAAAAAUUCAUGCUAGAGAGAAAUCAUAUGAAUGUAAGGAAUGUAGAAAGGCCUUUAGACAACAGUCAUACCUUAUUCAACAUCUGAGAAUUCACACUGGUGAGAGACCCUAUAAAUGUAUGGAAUGUGGAAAGGCCUUUUGUCGAGUGGGAGACCUUAGAGUACAUCACACAAUCCAUGCUGGGGAGAGACCCUAUGAAUGUAAAGAAUGUGGGAAGGCCUUUAGACUUCAUUAUCACCUUACUGAACAUCAGAGAAUACAUUCUGGUGUGAAACCCUACGAGUGUAAGGAAUGUGGGAAAGCCUUUAGUCGUGUUAGAGACCUUAGAGUACAUCAGACAAUUCAUGCUGGAGAGAGACCUUAUGAAUGUAAAGAAUGUGGGAAGGCCUUUAGACUUCAUUAUCAACUAACUGAACAUCAAAGAAUUCAUACUGGUGAGAGGCCUUAUGAAUGUAAGGUUUGUGGCAAGACCUUUAGGGUACAACGACAUAUUAGUCAACAUCAGAAAAUUCAUACUGGUGUCAAACCCUAUAAAUGUAAUGAAUGUGGGAAGGCCUUUAGUCAUGGCUCAUACCUUGUUCAACAUCAGAAAAUUCAUACUGGUGAAAAACCCUACGAAUGUAAAGAAUGUGGUAAGUCCUUUAGUUUUCAUGCAGAACUUGCUCGACAUCGUAGAAUUCAUACUGGUGAGAAACCCUAUGAAUGUAGAGAAUGUGGAAAAGCCUUUCGUCUUCAAACGGAACUUACUCGGCAUCAUAGAACUCAUACUGGUGAGAAACCCUAUGAAUGUAAGGAAUGUGGGAAGGCCUUUAUUUGUGGUUAUCAACUUACUUUACAUCUGAGAACUCACACCGGUGAGAUUCCCUAUGAAUGUAAGGAAUGUGGAAAAACCUUCAGUAGUCGCUAUCAUCUCACUCAACACUACAGAAUUCAUACUGGUGAGAAACCCUACAUAUGUAACGAAUGUGGAAAAGCCUUUCGUCUUCAAGGAGAACUUACCCGACAUCACAGAAUUCAUACAUGUGAGAAACCCUAUGAAUGUAAGGAAUGUGGGAAGGCUUUUAUUCAUAGCAAUCAAUUUAUUUCACACCAGCGAAUUCACACCAGUGAGAGCACCUACAUAUGUAAAGAAUGUGGGAAGAUUUUUAGUCGUCGCUAUAAUCUUACUCAACAUUUUAAAAUUCAUACUGGUGAAAAACCCUACAUAUGUAAUGAAUGUGGGAAAGCCUUUCGAUUUCAAACAGAACUUACUCAGCAUCACAGAAUUCAUACUGGUGAAAAACCCUAUAAAUGUACAGAAUGUGGGAAGGCCUUUAUUCGUAGCACUCAUCUCACGCAACAUCACAGAAUUCAUACUGGUGAGAAACCCUACGAAUGUACGGAAUGUGGGAAGACGUUUAGUCGGCACUAUCAUCUUACUCAACAUCACAGAGGCCAUACUGGUGAGAAGCCCUACAUAUGUAAUGAAUGUGGGAAUGCUUUUAUUUGCAGUUAUCGACUUACAUUACAUCAAAGAAUUCACACUGGUGAGCUUCCAUAUGAAUGUAAGGAAUGUGGAAAGACCUUUAGUCGUCGGUAUCAUCUUACUCAACAUUUUAGACUUCAUACUGGUGAGAAACCUUAUAGCUGUAAAGAAUGUGGGAAUGCCUUUCGUCUUCAAGCAGAACUUACUCGACAUCACAUAGUUCACACGGGUGAGAAACCCUAUAAAUGUAAAGAAUGUGGGAAAGCCUUCAGUGUUAAUUCAGAACUUACUCGACAUCACAGAAUUCAUACUGGUGAAAAACCCUAUCAAUGUAAAGAAUGUGGAAAAGCCUUUAUUCGUAGUGAUCAACUUACUUUACAUCAGAGAAAUCAUAUUAGUGAGGAAGUCCUAUGCAUAAUGUAAAGAGAAUACGAUGGCCUUUAGAAAAUGCCCUUUAGCAGAGAAUUUGUAAUUUAAGAAAUUUUCUGUUUGUUACGGAACAUGUGGGAAUCCCUUUUACUUCAUGCUCACAAUUUAUCAGAAAUUAUUUCGUAUGUUAAAGAGUCGAAAGACUAUAGCAUCACUCAGUCCCUGUUAGACUUUAGAAGAUUGAUACUGAUGCACUGCAUCCCAAACCAUCAAGGGCCUUUUCCCCUACAAACUGUUGUUGAACAGUGCUUCUCUAAAAUGCAAUAAUAAUGGGCCAGGUGAAGUGGCUCACACCUGUAAUCCCAGCACUGUGGAAAGACAGGAGUUCGAAACCAGCCUGGGCAACAUAGUGAGACCCUGCCUCAUGGCUUUAGUGAGCCAUGAUUGUGCCACUGCACUCCAGCUUGGUGACAGAGUGAGAUCCUGUCUCUAAAUAAAUAAAUAAAAUGCGGGCCAGGCACAGUGGCUCACACCUGUAAUCCCAGCACUAUGGGAGGCCCAGGUGAGCAGAUCACCUGAGGUCAGGAGUUCAAGACCAGCCUGGCCAACAUGGUGAAACCCCUUCUCUACUAAAAUACACAAAUUAGCUAGGCAUUGUGGGGGGUGCCUGUAAUCCCAGCUACUCAGGAGGCUGAGGCAGGAAAAUUGCAUGAACCUAAGUGGCAGAGGUUGCAGUGAGCUGAGAUCGCACCACUGCACUCUAGCUUGGGCAACAGAGCAAGACUCUGUCUCUUAAAUAAAUAAAUAAAUAGAUUACCAGAAAAAUGAAAAGAAAAAAACAGACAUACAAAAUAAAAGCCCCAGUUUUUUAUUAUGGUAUUUAACUGAGUUAACUCUGUCAGAUUGCUGCAAACAUUUCUAAAUACUUGCUCUUGGUAUCUAUAACUUUUGCAGAGACCAGAAGCAAACAAUUUGUGGGCCAGUGUCAACACAUGGACCACACUUUAUAUAGCACUGUAACGGAAAAUGAUUCUGUUAAUGUAAUGAACAUGGGAAAGACCAGCCUUGGCCUAUCUUUAUGAUAUAUAUAAAUAAUAUAAUUCUCAUAAUUCCACCUCUGCCUAUGUGGUGUUUGGCAAAACAUGCCCCUGUGCCUUGGUUUUUAAAAUGGUAAUAACAGUACCACCUAAUAGUAUUUUUGUGAGGAUGAAAUGCUAAUAAAAGAUAAAACCUUUAAAAGAGUAUUUGGCACACAGCAUUUUAUCAAUAAAUAUUGCUUUAUUUUUUUCAUUGGGGAUACAUUUAGUACAUUCAUGUGAGAGGAAGGCCCUGUGGGUGUAAGAAAUUUGUAAAAACUGUCCAUUACCUUUCACUCCUUAUUUAGAUUGGAAUAAUUAACUGGAGAUAAUAUCCAGUAAAAUAGAUUAAACUUCCAUUUAUAAAGUCAGAACCUAUCUCUGAAAAUUAAUGUGAGAAAGAAAUCUCUAGAUUUGAUGGGUGUGAAGAUUAUGAGAGUAAAGUUUUGAAGACUCAGGGAUAGCUGUAAUGCUUUUUUCUUUUUAUAACCCAAAAAGCAGGUAUGUCAGUCGCUUUUUCUGCCCACAAUGAUAAAUUAAAAACAGCCACUAUCCAUUUGGAAAACUUAAAAGAAUAAUGAACAGUUAUGUUCUAUCUAGAUUCAGCAAUUGUUAAUAUGUUGUCACAUUUGGUUUGCUUAUACAUAAUAUUUACAUAUUUUGCUGUAGUAUUUGAGUAUAAAUUGCAGAUACUAUAACACAUCACAUCUAAGAAUAAAGGCUGCCUCCUACUUAAUUGCUAUAUAACAAUUGUCCAACCUGUCUGUGCCCCAGGGCAGCUUUGAAUGCAGUCCAACAGAAAUUUGUAAGCUGUCUUAAAACAUGAGAUUUUUUUUGUGAUUUUUUUUAAGCUCAUCCGCCAUUGUUAGCACAUUUUAUGUGUAGCCCAAGAUAAUUCUUCUUCCAGUGUAACCCAGGGAAGCCAAAAGAUUUGACCCCCAGUAACUUCACACCUAAGGAGAUUAGCAAUAAUUCCAUAAUCUGUAAUAUUCAGUCUGUGUUCAUAUUCUCAGUUGUGUUCAUUCUUUUCAUUUGUGUAAACAAUGCUUUUCAUAGGUUAUUUUUAAAUUCAGGAACCAAAUUCAUGAAUUACAUUUGUGCAUUGUUCGUCUCUUUUAAAGUAAGAAUGGCCCUUCCCCCCACAACUUUAUUGCAACAUUGACUUUUUUUUUUUUUUUUUUUUUUUUUUUUUGAGAUGGAGUCUCUGUCGCCCAGGCUGGAGUGCAGUGGUGCGAUCUUGGCUCACUGCAAGCUCCGCCUCCCGGGUUCAGGCAAUUCUGCCUCAGCCUCCCCAGUAGCUGGGACUACAGGCGCCUUCAACCAUGCCCGGCUAAUUUUUUGUAUUUUUAGUAGAGACGGGGUUUCACCAUGUUAGCCAGGACGGUCUCGAUCUCCUGACCUGGUGAUCUGCCCGCCUCAGCCUCCCAAAGUGCUGGGAUUACAGGCAUGAGCCACCGCACCCGGCCUUCCCAAAGUAUUUUUAAAUGUGCUUUUUUAUCCCCAGUAUUUCCCAUUAACUGGAAUUUGGGAUUAGAGACCCAAUUAGGGACAGAUUAAAUAUUUUGGCAAGAAUACUUAAUGGGAGAAAUUUUGUAUUUCAAUUUGUAACCCAUUAGGUGGCAUACAAUGUCAUUAUACCACUAUGGUAUCCUUAGUUCAUUCACUUGGUGUAGCAGAACAUACAUUCCAAAGAUGGCCACACCAAUAUAUCCCAUUCUGCAUGUUCAUCUUACAAUGUGAUACCAACACUCCCCAAGAGGUAGAGCUCAUGGUCCUUCCUUUUGAAUCUGGCCAGGUGGGCCUGUGUUUAUGGCAGGAAUAACACUGUGAUUUCCACGACUAAGUCAUAAAAGGCAAUACAGCUUCUGCCUGACCCACUUGGGAUGAAGCCCAGCCACCAUGCUAUGAAGAUGCCAAGUAAUCACAUAGAAAAGCUAAGUAAAGCUGUCCUGAUUACAGCUGUAAUUGAGGUAACAGCCGGGAUCCAGCACCAAGUGUAUGAGGGUAUGAGCCUUCAGAUGAUUCUAACCCUUAGCCUUCAGGCUAUCCUAGCUGGUGCUAAGUGGAGCAGAGAAAAGCUUUCCCCCAUGAGCCUGCCCAAAUUGCAGAUUUACGUUUAAAAUAUGGCCUGUUUUAAGCCACUAAGUUUUGGAGUAGUUUGCCACACAGCGAUAGGUAACUGAAAUACUUGCUUCAUAUGGUAAUCACCAGGUUUCUCUGUUGUAGAGCUAAAUAUUUCUUUUAAUUUAGUAAACGAUCUGUAGAGUAGUACUUUGGCAUUUCGGAAAUUUAAAAUCUCCAAUAAUAUAAUGACACUAGAUCAAAAAGAAAAUGAAACCAUAAAGGACAAUUUAGAAAUGAAUGGUAAGAUCAGAAUUUGUGAAUGUGGCCAAACCUGUGCUCAGUGAAAAAUCAGUAACCUGUUAAUAUAUUCAGGAAACAAAUAUUGAGGGCCAGCACUUUGUUUCUCCUGCUCACCACUCUACUCCCAGUGACUUAAUACUGUCUCUUUAACAUAGUAAUCACUUAUAAAACUGUUAAAAGAAUGAAGAAGCAUUAAACUCAAGAAACUAAGGGAAAAAUAAGUCAAUAUAAGAAAGAAGGGAGGAUCAUUAAAAGGAGUUAAUGAAUUUGAAAAUAAAAUAGACUUAUUAAGGCUUUGUGAAAAAAUAUUAAUACUUGAUUUUAGUAUAGCUAAUCAAAGGAAAAAGAUAAUUACAGCAUUGUGAAUGAGAAUUGGAUGUAAGUACAGAUGGAGGAGAUAUUUUUUGUUUUAUUGAAAAUUUCAAGGAGGAAGUAAUAUCAAAAUUUCACUAGCUCUUUCUACACUGAUAUUAUAAUCCUGAUAAUACAACAGAUGAGGAUAGUUCUUAAAAGGCAAAAAUGUAGGUGAGUCAUUACGAAGAAAGCAGAAAUUCUAAACCAUCAGCACAUUCAUUCAAAAACCUAGUAAAGCAAUUAAGCAAAAUAAUUUGUUUACUUGGACUGUCCAGGGAUAGAUCUGUUCUAGUUUUCCAAAUUAAUGAUGGGAAAGGAAGAGCUGAUCCAGUCCAAGUAUCUUCAAGAUCCAUGUUCUCAGUUUUUCUUAGCUUUAAAUGGCCAAAUUGUGGCUUAGAUUGGAUAUGAUAAUUUCCUCAAUGCUUAACACUGAGCACAAUUUUUCACAUAUUUGAAAUCAAGGUGUAUCUUACAAUUUAUGGCAUCUGACAAUACUUCCAACCAGGUGGCAGUCAUCAAGCAGUUUUGUGAAAAGCCUUCCCGGUAAGAAUACAAAAGCAUCUGCACCAAAAUAUAUAGAUUUAAUGGCAUGUAGGGGUUUGCGUGAAUAUAUACAGUUGAAAUUCAAUUCUUCCUUAAAAAUAAUUGUAACUCAUUUCUUUAAGACUACCAUACUACCACUUUCCUCAACUUGGACUAAUGUCCAUUGUCAACCAAAAUGUCUGUGAUCUCAUGGAUCCAUUAUGAUUUGCAACUCCAGGUCCAUUUUAUGCAAAUAAGACAGCCAUAAUAUAUCAUUGUACAAGUCAUUUACUAUCUAAUUAUAUCAUUGCUCAACAUUUGCAAAUUAUUUUUACAAAUAACAAUAAUUGGAUGUAACAAAAAGCAGAGUAUUUUGAGACGUAUAUUAAUGCAAAAUAUUGUUAAUGUAUCAGUGGAUUGUUCCUCCAAAGUACCAGUGCCUUAACACAACAUAUCUAAAAGAACAUCUCUGGGAACAGUAGUACUUAAUGGCAACUUGAGAAUUGGUUUGUGGGCACACAGCCUUGUGAAGUUUUGAAUACUAAAUCCCUUUUUUAAAAAAGUGCUUAUUAUCAGGCUAUCAAUCAAAAGAUUUGAGUCUUUCAGUAAAGAAAAUUUGCUUAAUUUUAUCUAGUGCAUGAUAAACUUUACUAAGGAAGUCUCAUUCAGAAUAUCUAAUAUUUUGGAUGUGAGCCCACACUGGAAAUGCCAUAACCAAAAAAGAGUGACCCUAAAGAUAGAAUAUUCAGAUCUAAUGGCAGAUGCUUAGCUAUGCUGGGAAAGGAAGUGAAUUGUAUAUUGCUCUGCUGCUCACAUAUUCCUCUGCAAUAAAUUGCUGGCCCAGUUUAGUUUUUAUAUACUCACUACUAUACUAAUGAGGAUGGCUCAAUUUUUUAUUUGAACGUACUAUAAUGAAUUUAAACUUUCAUUGGUAUUUAUGUUUUAACAGGUUUUCACUAUUUCAAAUAUACUUCAAUAAAUAUCCUUGUCUGUGA